AUGGAUGCACAGCAGGACAGACCCAAGUCCCAAGACUGCCUGGGCCUAGUGGCCCCCCUAGCAUCUGCUGCAGAGGUCCCCUCUACAGCUCCCGUGUCUGGGAAGAAGCACAGACCACCAGGACCCCUGUUCUCCUCCUCAGAUACCCUUCCUGCCACCUCUUCCCACUCCCGGGACUCAGCCCAGGUCACCUCGAUGAUUCCUGCCCCCUUCACAGCUGCAAGCAGGGAUGCCGGCAUGAGAAGAACAAGGUCGGCUCCUGCAGCUGCCGCAGCAGCCCCUCCCCCCUCCACAUUGAACCCCACGUCGGGGUCACUACUCAAUGCAGUGGAUGGAGGCCCCUCACAUUUCUUGGCCUCAGCCACAGCUGCAGCACGUGCCCAGAGGUCAGAAGUGAGAUAUAACCAGAGAUCCCAGACCUCCCGGACCAGAUCCUGCCUCAAACGAAAUGCCAGCUCCAGCUCCCACAGCUCUACGGAAGGCCUCCCGGAACUAAAGCGGAGGAGGGGGCCAGCCUCAUCCCACUGCCAGCUGGCCCACAGUUCCUCAAAGACAGUGAGUGAGGACGGAGCUCAGGCUGUCUCUACGGGUCACCGCUGUGAAAAGAAGGCAGAUACAGCACCAGGGCAGACACUCGCCCCCAGGGGUGGCUCCCCCAGAUCCCAGGCCUCUAGGCCCCACAUCAACAGUGCACUGCACGUUGAGGACAAGGCCAUCUCGGACUGCAGACCCUCACGGCCUUCCCACACUUUGUCCUCACUUGCAACGGGGGCUUCGGGUGGGCCUCCCGUUUCUAAAGCACCCACUAUGGAUGCACAGCAGGACAGACCCAAGUCCCAAGACUGCCUGGGCCUAGUGGCCCCCCUAGCAUCUGCUGCAGAGGUCUCCUCUACAGCUCCCGUGUCUGGGAAGAAGCACAGACCACCAGGACCCCUGUUCUCCUCCUCAGAUCCCCUUCCUGCCACCUCUUCCCACUCCCGGGACUCAGCCCAGGUCACCUCGCUGAUUCCUGCCCCCUUCACAGCUGCAAGCAGGGAUGCCAGCAUGAGAAGAACAAGGCCUGGCACCUCCGCUCCUGCAGCUGCAGCAGCAGCCCCUCCCCCCUCCACAUUGAACCCCACGUCGGGGUCACUACUCAAUGCAGUGAAUGGAGGCCCCUCACAUUUCUUGGCCUCAGCCACAGCUGCAGCACGUGCCCAGAGGUCAGAAGUGAGAUAUAACCAGAGAUCCCAGACCUCCCGGACCAGAUCCUGCCUCCAAGGAAAUGCCAGCUCCAGCUCCCACAGUUCUACGGAAGGCCUCCCGGAACUAAAGCGGAGGAGGGGGCCAGCCUCAUGCCACUGCCAGCUGGCCCUCAGUUCCUCAAACACAGUGAGUGAGGACGGACCUCAGGCUGUCUCUUCGGGUCACACCCGCUGUCAAAAGGCAGAUACAGCACCAGGGCAGACACUCGCCCCCAGGGGUGGCUCCCCCAGAUCCCAGGCCUCUAGGCCCCACAUCAACAGUGCACUGCACGUUGAGGGCAAGGCCAUCUCGGACUGCAGACCCUCACGGCCUUCCCACACUUUGUCCUCACUUGCAACGGGGGCUUCGCGUGGGCCUCCCCUUUCUAAAGCACCCACUAUGGAUGCACAGCAGGACAGACCCAAGUCCCAAGACUGCCUAGGCCUAGUGGCCCCCCUAGCAUCUGCUGCAGAGGUCUCCUCUACAGCUCCCGUGUCUGGGAAGAAGCACAGACCACCAGGACCCCUGUUCUCCUCCUCAGAUCCCCUUCCUGCCACCUCUUCCCACUCCGGGGACUCAGCCCAGGACACCUCGCUGAUUCCUGCCCCCCUCACACCUGCAAGCAGGGAUGCCGGCGUGAGAAGAAUGUUUUGUGUUCGAAAUUGUUUGAGGGGUUUGGGUUUAUUUUUGUUGGUUUUUUCUUUUUUGUUUUUGCUUACAUGGGCAUCCUUCAGCUUUUAAUAAUCUGAAAAGCUCUA